GCGCCCUGGCAAUGCAGAGGAGUCACCGAGCUCCGCCUUUGACCAGCGUGCAGCUGGGAGAGUGAGAUCAGAGACCACAGCAGAUCGUGGCGCUGUGAUCAGGGGGUACACUCAAGCUGUGGGUCCCUUACCCCAGCCUUGAGAUCCCAGGAAGGCCUGCAGCCUGAAACGGGCCUUGAAAGGUGCGUAGUUUCUCUGAAAAGCAUCACCCAGGUCAGAAUGAAAGGAAACUCUCUGUGCAGACCGCUGUAUGUGGGACCUUUGAAGACAGUCAAAUAGUGUUCAAUUCUAUAGUAAGCAGAUUUUCUUGUUCUCUCUGGAGAAUACAGUUUUUGGUAAAAAAUUGAUCAGGUUAUCUUAUUCAUAAAUCGUCUUGAGAGGCAGGUCACAGUUCCCUCAUCUGUAAAAGGCAGAUUACAGCCCACCUUCUGUGAGCCCCUUGAGGGAGAGCUUAGAGCCCUGCAGAGUGUGUGGCAUAUGGUAUGCCCUUAAAAAGCAUCAGUAGAGCAAAUGGAUAUGUCACAAGGUUAUCAUGAGGCUAUGACAGUAGAACUGUCCCGGGAGUUCUGUGAGCUGUGCAGCUUCAUGUAGGUUAGUUAAUUUGCCAAGUAUAGUAUAUGCUGUCCUUAUGCAACUGGCAAGGAUGAAUCUUAGUUUCCAAUGCAUUUAUUAUUAUUAAUUUCAAAAAAAGAAAUAUGUAACACAGACUCUGGGAGGCAAGGUCAUCUCCUUAACUACGCUUAAUAGAGAGGGGAGGUGAGGUGCUGGCACCUGGGAAUGUCUUUGUGUCAGCUUUUACUUAAAGGUAUUUCAAAACUUCAAGAAAAAUGCACAUUUCUGAGAGGUGUGUAUAUCUUAGCCCUACCAAGUAUAGAAUGUGAAACUGAGAGGGUUACUGAAUCUUAGUAUCUCGACUGAAAAGCCAAUGUGUCAUAGUAUAUUUUGCUAAAAUCUUGACUCAAUUGAAGAGAAGUAAGGCCCUUAAAAUUUUGAGAACUAGGUGACGUGUCUGAAAAUUUUGAGAAAAGUGCUUUUCACACCUGUAGGACAAGAAGGUUUCUGCCUUUUUUGCUUAUUGGGUUAACUUUCUAUAAUUUAAUAGGAAAGAAUGAAAAGGAAUAGUAUCCAAGGGAAAAGUUAAUUGAUGAUUUUUAUUUCUAUUUUGCAUAAAGUGAUUUAAUGUUGCAUUUCCUGAUGUAACUGUAACCAAUAUCAAAGUUGCUUUUCCUGGCUGGGCAUGGUGGCUCACAGCUGUAAUCCCAGCACUUUGGGAGGCCAAGGCGGGAGGAUCGCCUGAGAGCAGGAGUUUGAGACCAGCCUGGCCAACAUGGCAAGAUCCUGUCUCUACAAAAAAUGAAAUUAGCUGGGUGUAGUGGCACAUGCCUGUAGUCCCAGCUACUCGGGGAGGCUGAGGUGUGAGGUCAAGACUGCAGAGCCAUGUUUGUGCCACUGCACUCCAGCCUGGGGGAUCUUCUCUGGAUCAAGCAAUGGUGGUGAAAAAUGUUUCGCAAGGGCAAAAAACGACACAGUAGUAGCAGUUCCCAAAGUAGCGAAAUCAGUACUAAGAGCAAGUCUGUGGAUUCUAGCCUUGGGGGUCUUUCACGAUCCAGCACUGUGGCCAGCCUCGACACAGAUUCCACCAAAAGCUCAGGACAAAGCAACAAUAAUUCAGAUACCUGUGCAGAAUUUCGAAUAAAAUAUGUUGGUGCCAUUGAGAAACUGAAACUCUCCGAGGGAAAAGGCCUUGAAGGGCCAUUAGACCUGAUAAAUUAUAUAGACGUUGCCCAGCAAGAUGGAAAGUUGCCUUUUGUUCCUCCGGAGGAAGAAUUUAUUAUGGGAGUUUCCAAGUAUGGCAUAAAAGUAUCAACAUCAGAUCAAUAUGAUGUUUUGCACAGGCAUGCUCUCUACUUAAUAAUCCGGAUGGUGUGUUACGAUGACGGUCUGGGGGCGGGAAAAAGCUUACUGGCUCUGAAGACCACAGAUGCAAGCAAUGAGGAAUACAGCCUGUGGGUUUAUCAGUGCAACAGCCUGGAACAAGCACAAGCCAUUUGCAAGGUUUUAUCCACCGCUUUUGACUCUGUAUUAACAUCUGAGAAACCCUGAAUCCUGCAAUCAAGUAGAAGUCAACUUCAUCUGAAAGUUCAGCUGUUUUCAAACUGCAAUGCUGAAAUGUUAUGCAAAUAAUGAAGUUAUCCCUUGCUCUAGAUUUUCUGAAGAAAAUGGAUUGUGUAAAAUGCUGAUCAUUUGUUUAUUAAAAUGUGUCCUAUUACACAGUGAGUUAACUCUCAAUGAAGUCAUCUAUUUUCUGGGCUAAAAAACUUCAUUUGUCUUUUUCAACUUCUAAUAAGCUUAACCUAAGUGUCACAGAAGCCUAGGUGUCACAGAGGUCCACUCAGUGACAAACACACACUGAAGGCCUGAGGAAGACGAGAUGUCACAGAGGUCCACUCAGUGACAAACACACACUGAAGGCCUGAGGAAGACUAGAUGUCACAGAGGUCCACUCAGUGACAAACACACACUGAAGGCCUGAGGAAGACGAGAUGUCACAGAGGUCCACUCAGUGACAAACACACACUGAAGGCCUGAGGAAGACUAGAUGUCACAGAGGUCCACUCAGUGACAAACACACACUGAAGGCCUGAGGAAGACGAGAUGUCACAGAGGUCCACUCAGUGACAAACACACACUGAAGGCCUGAGGAAGACGAGAUGUCACAGAGGUCCACUCAGUGACAAACACACACUGAAGGCCUGAGGAAGACUAGAUGUCACAGAGGUCCACUCAGUGACAAACACACACUGAAGGCCUGAGGAAGACGAGAUGUCACAGAGGUCCACUCAGUGACAAACACACACUGAAGGCCUGAGGAAGACGAGAUGUCACAGAGGUCCACUCAGUGACACACACUGAAGGCCUGAGGAAGACUGAGGACAUGGGCUCAGUGGUGGCUUCCCAGUCAUGGUAUCACUGGCAUGGACCUCUGUCCGGCAGAGGUGUGGACUGGAGACCAGGAUUCAUGCUGGUCUGGAACAGUGACAUUGCCAACUUAAGACACACAAAGCAGAUUUUCAGAAGUGUCUGGUCAAGAUAACAUGCUGGCCAACCACAAUUCCUAGAGUUAAGAGAACCUUAAAAGAUUACCGCUCAUGCUAAAAGUAUGUAAAGAUCCCAUGUACAGUAUGAUAGUGUACUUUUUUUAAAGGACUGUCAAUAUACAAAACUUUAAAGAUUAAAAACAUUAAAAAUAAAACCAUGUCCAUUUAAAAGUAUUUUAUUUUUUUCCAGUCAAAUGACUAGUUAACAAGAAGAGUAAACUUAUUAAACAUGCUCUAAUUAUAAAUCACUGCAUUAAGGACAAUGAAAAUAAUCAAUUUCGGUUAUACAAUAUAUACAGUUGUGCUGCAACCAAAGUAAUCAGGUGAAUGAACUGAAUAUCAUACAUCUCAAAAUAGCAUCCUAAGCUGCAUAUUAUGUUAUCCACCCCUUAACAGAUCACACAGUUACUCUUAGUCUGUGUACAUGUUCUGAGCCAUCAUCCCAGAUCUGAUGGAGAAUGGCAUGCAAAAUGCCAGAAUCCUGCAGCUGCAGUUCAUGAAACAUAAACUUUAAAUAUAAAUAGAUAUCUACAAUGUUUUUCUUUCUCUUAGUUGCUUUUUUAAUUUGCAAGGAGCAAAUAACUAAGAAAGGAUAUUAGCAGGGUCGUUAAUAUAAUUUCUCCUCUGGUAAGAGUACUAUUAGUUACUGCACAAUAGCACCAAAUUGUAGACUGGAAAAAUAUUUCCUAGGUAUUUAUGUACCAGUGAACCUGACAGAUUAGUUUGGGACUGGAGUUCUAAUGUUGAUAUGAAUCAACUUUAUUCCUUAUAUAGCUGGCACCAGGUGGUCAAAAGGCUGACUAUAAAAUACAGAUGCAGGAGGAUUGUUAAAAUAGACAUAAGUGCACUGUGCAAAAUACAUCUGUUUACUUAAAUCUAUGAGAAAAUUAAAUGAAGGGUUCAAACAGAAAUUAACAAUUAGUGAAAACAGAUGUAGUGCUUUAAAAAAAAACAAAAACAAAAAACUACAGAUAUAACACAUUUUUACCCGGAACUUUGAAAGGUAAAAAGCGAUUGCUAUACAACAUCAUAAAACAUUCCAGUUUGUUCUGUCUUCCUUUAUAACAAAAACAAAAAGUACAAUGCCAAAAAAAAAAAAAACUCUACACAGUCUUGCAUAAUAAAGACAAGCUGCUUCAAUCAAAUGCACCAUCACAACAAAUGCAGUUAACAGCAUUGCUGCCUCACUUUCCAAGCCUAUAUGCAAAUUUAUUCCUUUACUUUUGUUAAAAGUCCAAGUGGGUAUCAUAUGCCUAUUUAUUCUCAGAGUGCCAAAAUUUCCAAUAUUCCUACUAUGAAUCUUACCCUCGCAAUUACUAAAUAGAGGUAUGACAGUCAAGUUCAUUAAACGAAUGAGUUUUGGUUUUAUAAUAGACAACCUAAUCCUCUACUACCACCCCAAGUAGCUUAAGAAUGAUAUGAUGGCCUGAAACAGUAAAAAGUGGGAUGUUUGGGAGUAUUACCUGGGACCUAUAUAUUUCUGAUAUGUUCUUGAUUAUAAACAGAUGGACAGAUUCAAUUUCAAGACAGUGUGACUACCAUUCCUGUUGGAGUAUUAUAGAAAUACAAGACACUAAACUGAGUAAACAUUCUCCUGGGCUAGAAGGGAAGGCAGUGGUACACUCAGUAGGAAACAGCAAGUGAUGUGUUAAUACAGCAUGGUCUGCGCCACAGAAUUCUACUGUGUACAGUUGCUUUCUGUGUGACUCAGGAAGUUCAAGAAGGCAAAUUCCAAAACACCUAAAGCAUAUAAACUAAUUUAAAAGAACUGUUUUGCAAUCCAUCAUCCUUAGUUUUUAACCAAAUUCAGGAAAUGCAGUUUUAUAUAACCUGGAACAGAAUGAACUGUAGUUACCCUACGUUGUCAUAAACCAUCAGUAGUUUUGUUAAGUAUGAUUGUUCACAACAGGUUAUACAUACAUGCAGAAUAUAAUGAUAGCUGCAACCUCACAAAUUAGGGCUAGAAAGUACAAUGCUAAUGUGUAAAUUUCCAAGUUGCUUUUUAAACACUGGGUGGAUUUCAAAGGAAUGUGUGUCUUUAAAGGUGAACUGAUGGCAUUUUAUCGAGAAAGUUCAGAGCUGGGCUAUGGACUUCUGAAGCAGCAGUUCACUGGCCGCCUAAAAUAAUAAUUGUGAUAAAGGUCACCAACUCCAGAACUGGGCCAAGGAAUGCAGGAAGAAUUUAUUCAUUAAUGCAAACAUUUUUAGGUUUAGCUAAUUCCGUAGAGGCAGGAUCUUGAUUAUGUAUAAUAGUUAAAAUAACUUUUCAGUUCACCUGUUGGGAAAUUCAGUUUUUCCUAAUAAAUGCAUAGCAAUGUUUCAUGAAAACCACAAAUUAUAAAAACAAUUACUGAUAUGUAAAAA